AGUCUGUAGGUGACUACAGAAGGAGGAGGAGCUCCGUCUGUUCUCUCUUCAGGCAGUUGUUGUGUCUCUCAGCGCUUGUUGGGUUCACAACCUAUUAAAUAAGCCAGCUGGUCUUCACCCUCCCAGACAAGUCAACUCAGGGGAGGCAGCAGGGUGUGGGCCUUGACCCGCAGCCCUAGCCGGGGCCGGGGCCGGGGCCAGGGAUGGUGCCCGGGGCCGCGCUGUGAGGUGGGCAGGCGAGGAGCGGGAAGACCAUCUCUGCAAGUGCAGCAUAGCCUCGGCCUAGGACAGUGGGAGUGUGUGGCCAAAGCUGUGAGCAGAGGCACAGGUGGUGGCAGACAGUAGAGGCGCCCCAUGGGGAACAUACUGACCUGUUGUGUGCACCCUAGCGUCAGCCUCGAGUUUGACCAGCAACAGGGGUCGGUGUGUCCCUCUGAAUCUGAGAUCUAUGAGGCAGGAGCUGGGGACAGGAUGGCAGGAGCGCCCAUGGCUGCUGCUGUGCAGCCUGCUGAGGUGACCGUUGAAGUUGGUGAGGACCUCCACAUGCACCACAUUCGUGACCAGGAGAUGCCUGAAGCUUUGGAGUUUAGCCUUUCUGCCAAUCCAGAGGCAAGCACAAUAUUCCAGAGGAACUCUCAAACAGAUGCUUUGGAGUUUAACCCUUCUGCCAAUCCAGAGGCAAGCACAAUAUUCCAGAGGAACUCUCAAACAGAUGUUGUAGAAAUAAGAAGAAGCAACUGUACAAACCAUGUAUCUACUGAGCGUUUCAGUCAACAAUACAGCUCGUGUUCGACAAUAUUCCUUGAUGACAGCACAGCCAGCCAGCAUUAUCUUACAAUGACAAUAAUAUCUGUGACCUUGGAGAUACCUCAUCAUAUCACACAAAGAGAUGCAGAUAGAUCUUUGAGCAUACCUGAUGAACAGUUACACUCAUUUGCGGUUUCCACCGUGCACAUUACGAAGAACAGAAAUGGAGGUGGGAGUUUAAAUAACUAUUCCUCCUCCAUUCCAUCGACUCCCAGCACCAGCCAGGAGGACCCUCAGUUCAGUGUUCCUCCCACUGCCAACACACCCACCCCCGUUUGCAAGCGGUCCAUGCGCUGGUCCAACCUGUUUACAUCUGAGAAAGGGAGUCACCCAGACAAAGAGAGGAAAGCCCCGGAGAAUCAUGCUGACACCAUCGGGAGCGGCAGAGCCAUCCCCAUUAAACAGGGCAUGCUCUUAAAGCGAAGUGGGAAAUGGCUGAAGACAUGGAAAAAGAAAUACGUCACCCUGUGUUCCAAUGGCGUGCUCACCUAUUAUUCAAGCUUAGGUGAUUAUAUGAAGAAUAUUCAUAAAAAAGAGAUUGACCUUCGGACAUCUACCAUCAAAGUCCCAGGAAAGUGGCCAUCCCUAGCCACAUCGGCCUGUGCACCCAUCUCCAGCUCUAAAAGCAAUGGCCUAUCCAAGGACAUGGACACCGGGCUGGGUGACUCCAUAUGCUUCAGCCCCAGUAUCUCCAGCACCACCAGCCCCAAGCUCAACCCGCCCCCCUCUCCUCAUGCCAAUAAAAAGAAACACCUAAAGAAGAAAAGCACCAACAACUUUAUGAUUGUGUCUGCCACUGGCCAAACAUGGCACUUUGAAGCCACGACGUAUGAGGAGCGGGAUGCCUGGGUCCAAGCCAUCCAGAGCCAGAUCCUGGCCAGCCUGCAGUCAUGCGAGAGCAGUAAAAGCAAGUCCCAGCUGACCAGCCAGAGCGAGGCCAUGGCCCUGCAGUCGAUCCAAAACAUGCGUGGGAACGCCCACUGUGUGGACUAUGAGACCCAGAAUCCUAAGUGGGCCAGUUUGAACUUGGGAGUCCUCAUGUGUAUUGAAUGCUCAGGAAUCCACCGCAGUCUUGGCACCCGCCUUUCCCGUGUGCGAUCUCUGGAGCUGGAUGACUGGCCAGUUGAGCUCAGGAAGGUUAUGUCAUCUAUUGGCAAUGACCUAGCCAACAGCAUCUGGGAAGGGAGCAGCCAGGGGCAGACAAAACCCUCAGUAAAGUCCACGAGGGAAGAGAAGGAACGGUGGAUCCGUUCCAAAUAUGAGGAGAAGCUCUUUCUGGCCCCACUACCCUGCACUGAGCUGUCCCUGGGCCAGCACCUGCUGCGGGCCACCGCUGAUGAGGACCUGCAGACAGCCAUCCUGCUGCUGGCACAUGGCUCCCGUGAGGAGGUGAACGAGACCUGUGGGGAGGGAGACGGCUGCACGGCGCUCCAUCUGGCCUGCCGCAAGGGGAAUGUGGUCCUGGCACAGCUCCUGAUCUGGUACGGGGUGGACGUCAUGGCCCGAGAUGCCCACGGGAACACAGCGCUGACCUACGCCCGGCAGGCCUCCAGCCAGGAGUGCAUCAACGUGCUUCUGCAGUACGGCUGCCCCGACGAGUGCGUGUAGUAUCUGUUUUAUUUGACUGCAGUCUCCUUGGUGCAAAAACAAAAUGGGAAAAAUAAGGAUAACUCAGAAUUUCAAAAGGAAAUCACAAAUUCAGCUAGUAAUAGCAUUUUCAGUACUUUUCAUAAACUAAGUAAAUACACAAAAUGUUGAUUUUUCUGACCAUAAGACAUAUUUUAUGUCCUUUUGCCAAGGUGGAUGUGUUAGUCUCAGGCCCUCCUGGCCACAUUGCCCAAGUCACACAGGCUUCUGUAUUAUGUAUUUAGAUAAAAUGUGUGAAAAUAUAUUUGAAAAAAAAGUUCAUAAA